UUUUUUUUUUUUUUUUUUUUUUUUUAGACAAGGUCUCAUUCUGUUGCCCAGGCUAGAGUGCAGUGGUGUGAACAUGGCUUACUGCAGGCUCAGGUGAUUCUUCCACCUUAGCCUCCUGAGUAGCUGGGACUACAGGCACACACCACCAUGCCGGGCUAUUUUUUUUUCUUUUUUUGUAUAUUUUUGUAGAGAUGGGGUUUUGCCCUGUUGCCCAGACUGGUCUCGAACUCCUAGGCUCAAACCAUCAGCCCGCCUAGACGUCUCAAACUGUUGGGAUUACAGGCAUGAGCCACUGUGCCAGCCUAGAGUAAGAUUCUUUAAAAGGAAGUACUAGCCUGAGAGAGUAUGUUUCACUCUAUAUGGUAGUUGAGUUUGGGUUCUAGAAUUAAUCUACUUGAGUUGGAAUCUCAGCUCUAGUUCUUUUUUUUUUUUUUUUGAGACAGAGUCUCGCACUGUCGUCUGGGCUGGAGUACAGUGGCGCGAUCUCAGCUCACUGUAACCUCCGCCUCCUGGGUUCAAGUGGAUUUUUCUGCCUUAGCCUCCUGAGUAGCAGAGACUGUAUACAGGCACCUGCCACCACACAUGGCUGAUUUUUUGUAUUUUUAGAAGAGACAGGGUUUCACUAUGUUGGCCAGGCUGGUCUCAAACUCCUGACCUCAUGAUCCGCCCACCUCAGCCUCCCAAAGUGCUGGGAUUGCAGGCAGAGCCACCGUGCCCAGCCAACUCUAGCUCUUAAAAGCAAAAUCACUGGUAAGUCUCUAUGCCUGAAUCUCAGUUUCCUCAUCUCUAAAAUGACGGUAGUACUACUACUUAUUUCACAGGGUGGUUGGUGUACACUUGCACAUAGUAAAUAUUUGAUAAAUGUUAUCCAAUAUGUUUAUAUUCUUUACUAAAAAUAUAUUUUAUUAAAUGUACUACAUGUAAAAGGACUUUUAAUAGCAUAUUAAGAAAAUAUUUUCUAAGCCGGGUGUGGUGGCUGACGCCUGUAAUCCCAGCACUUUGGGAGGUCGAGGCAGGUGGAUCACUUGAGGUCAGGAAUUUGAGACCAGCCUGGCCAACAUGGGGAAACCCUGUCUCUACUAAAAAUACAGCAAUUAGCCGAGUGUGGUGGCGCAUGCCUGUAAUCCCAGCUACUCGAGAGGCUGAGGCAUGAGAAUCACUUGAACCUGGGAGGCAGAGAUUGCAGUGAGCUGAGAUCGCGCCAUUGCACUCCAGCCUGGGCAACAGAGCGAGACUGUCAAAAAAAAAAGGAAAUUAUUUUCUUAUCCAUCAAUAAAUAAAUACAUUUACAUAAUCUUUAAUGGCUGUGUAAUAUUUCAACUUGCUGUUUGCUAUCAUUUACUUAACUGAUCAUUUUUAUGCAUAUAGAAUUAUAUGUGAUAUAUUUGCUUAUUUUAACAUUUUGUAAUAACACCUUGAAUGUGAAUCUGUGUAAUACUCUUGUUUCAAGCAACAAUAACUAAAACACAUAAAAAAUUGUGUAGAAGUUUUCUGUAGCAUUUAAAUUUCAUUUUCAUUUCAUGUUUAGGGGUUGAGAUAGAGGCUGUUUCUCAGAGCAGAAAGAUGUAAAUUGCUGUCAUGUGCCACUGGUCAGGAAUGGUGUACAUCAGUUGAUACUUCUGAAGCACUGGGCCACCUGCUGGAAUUUGUAUAGGAAUGUUAUCCUGAAUUUCGGUUUUAUUUUACAAUGAUAACAUAAGUUUAAAGCACAUGCAGAGAAAUCUGUGUUCAAAAGCAUUUAUGCUACUUUUGAGUUGCAGGGACAGUAUUAUAAAAUCUUUUUGUGGGGUGAAGGAAGAUGGGAUGUCUGAGUAUUUUUUUUUUCUCUCAAGCAGUCUCAUUCCAAUCAGCAGUGUAAUUGGAAUGCAACUCCAAUCUGGAGGAGGAAGGGGAAUUUUUGGCAAGGAUAUACUAAGUAGUUGGGAGCUUUAUUCACAUUAAGCGUAGAUAGCCAUUCAUUAUGAAAACAACUCAGUAAGAACAAGCAUAGCAUUCUCUUUCUACAGCUGCGAUUUACUCUGAUACUAUUACCUGGUUUGUUGCAUAUAGAUAACUCCUUUCCUACCAGAAAAAUAAAUUAUUGACCUAAAUGAAAAUGGUAGUAUUUACUGCCAUCUGUACUUCUGCAAAUGGUUUUCUCUAAUCGCUGCCUCAAAUGAAGUAUAAGAUUUCCAUAAAGUUUAAAACCGUAUCUUGAGAAAACAACAAUAAAAGGCAUUUAUGACAUGGUAUUUGAAUUAUACCUGACCUGUGAGCUCUGAGAGCAAAGGACUAUGUCUUAUUUUUCUUUGUAUCUGCAGAAACUGUCAUAGCACUUGGCACAAAGUGAGUGUUCAGGAAAUGUUGAAUGAGAGAGUGAAUGAUGUAGGAGUAUUCCUUUCUCCCUAAGUAUCUCAAGAUGAUCACACCUGCAUCUGUGUGAAAUGCAGAGGCUUUAUCCAAUAUGGCUGAUGUCAGUUCAUUUUGAUCAUCUCUGCUAAUCAUUUCAAACCAUCUGUCUGAAAAAGGAGUGAGUACAAUAGCUAGAACAAGCUAGGUUCUGGGAGUGUAGACUUAAGAAUGAAAUGCUUUGAAGGAAUUUGAGAAGGGUAGUAACAUGAUGAAGUAGUAUAAGCAGACUUAAUCUAGUACAAAUAUAUGGGCUGUUUGAGACAUUGUCCCUGGUGGAUUCUGCAGCAUGGUACUGUGGUGGUGUAAUGCUACAUUUGUAGUUAGCACUAAUAAAAAUUGACUUGUGCCUACUAAAUAUCUGUAGUCCAGUAUAAUGUUUUGCUUUAACACAAAAAUUGGUGAAAAUUAAUUGAAUUAAUUCAGAUACUUCAGAUUUUUGUGCCUUUCUGUAUAUAUAAUUUCAAUUCCAUAUAUAUAAGCUUACUAAACAUUAAAGAUAUUGAAAUACUGAUUGCUGUCUAGGCCAGGGGUCCUCAACCCUGGGCCAUGGGCUGCACAGCAGGAGAUGAGCCAGUGAAGCAUCAUCUGUAUUUACAACCACUUCCCAUCGUGUAUUACCACCUGAGCUCAGCCUCCUCUCAGAUCAGCAGCGGCAAUAGAUUCUCAUAGGAGUGUUAACCCUACUGUGAACUGCGCAUGCGAGGGAUCUAGGUUGCCCCUCCUUAUAAGAAUCUAAUGCCUGAUGAUCUGUCACUGUCUUUCUUCACUCCCAGAUGGGACUGUCUAGUUGCAGGAAAACAAGCUCAGGGCUCCCACUGAUUCUACAUUAUGUACUCUGUGCAAAAAACCUGGUGAAAAAGGAUUUUUUCCGACUUCCUGAUCCAUUUGCUAAGGUGGUGGUUGAUGGAUCUGGGCAAUGCCAUUCUACAGAUACUGUGAAGAAUACGCUUGAUCCAAAGUGGAAUCAGCAUUAUGACCUGUAUAUUGGAAAGUCUGAUUCAGUUACGAUCAGUGUAUGGAAUCACAAGAAGAUCCAUAAGAAACAAGGUGCUGGAUUUCUCGGUUGUGUUCGUCUUCUUUCCAAUGCCAUCAACCGCCUCAAAGACACUGGUUAUCAGAGGUUGGAUUUAUGCAAACUCGGGCCAAAUGACAAUGAUACAGUUAGAGGACAGAUAGUAGUAAGUCUUCAGUCCAGAGACCGAAUAGGCACAGGAGGACAAGUUGUGGACUGCAGUCGUUUAUUUGAUAACGAUUUACCAGACGGCUGGGAAGAAAGGAGAACCGCCUCUGGAAGAAUCCAGUAUCUAAACCAUAUAACAAGAACUACGCAAUGGGAGCGCCCAACACGACCGGCAUCCGAAUAUUCUAGCCCUGGCAGACCUCUUAGCUGCUUUGUUGAUGAGAACACUCCAAUUAGUGGAACAAAUGGUGCAACAUGUGGACAGUCUUCAGAUCCCAGGCUGGCAGAGAGGAGAGUCAGGUCACAACGACAUAGAAAUUACAUGAGCAGAACACAUUUACAUACUCCUCCAGACCUACCAGAAGGCUAUGAACAGAGGACAACGCAACAAGGCCAGGUGUAUUUCUUACAUACACAGACUGGUGUGAGCACAUGGCAUGAUCCAAGAGUGCCCAGGGAUCUUAGCAACAUCAAUUGUGAAGAGCUUGGUCCAUUGCCUCCUGGAUGGGAGAUCCGUAAUACGGCAACAGGCAGAGUUUAUUUCGUUGACCAUAACAACAGAACAACACAAUUUACAGAUCCUCGGCUGUCUGCUAACUUGCAUUUAGUUUUAAAUCGGCAGAACCAAUUGAAAGACCAACAGCAACAGCAAGUGGUAUCGUUAUGUCCUGAUGACACAGAAUGCCUGACAGUCCCAAGGUACAAGCGAGACCUGGUUCAGAAACUAAAAAUUUUGCGGCAAGAACUUUCCCAACAACAGCCUCAGGCAGGUCAUUGCCGCAUUGAGGUUUCCAGGGAAGAGAUUUUUGAGGAAUCAUAUCGACAGGUCAUGAAAAUGAGACCAAAAGAUCUCUGGAAGCGAUUAAUGAUAAAAUUUCGUGGAGAAGAAGGCCUUGACUAUGGAGGCGUUGCCAGGGAAUGGUUGUAUCUCUUGUCACAUGAAAUGUUGAAUCCAUACUAUGGCCUCUUCCAGUAUUCAAGAGAUGAUAUUUAUACAUUGCAGAUCAAUCCUGAUUCUGCAGUUAAUCCGGAACAUUUAUCCUAUUUCCACUUUGUUGGACGAAUAAUGGGAAUGGCUGUGUUUCAUGGACAUUAUAUUGAUGGUGGUUUCACAUUGCCUUUUUAUAAGCAAUUGCUUGGGAAGUCAAUUACCUUGGAUGACAUGGAGUUAGUAGAUCCGGAUCUUCACAACAGUUUAGUGUGGAUACUUGAGAAUGAUAUUACAGGUGUUUUGGACCAUACCUUCUGUGUUGAACAUAAUGCAUAUGGUGAAAUUAUUCAGCAUGAACUUAAACCAAAUGGCAAAAGUAUCCCUGUUAAUGAAGAAAAUAAAAAAGAAUAUGUCAGGCUCUAUGUGAACUGGAGAUUUUUACGAGGCAUUGAGGCUCAAUUCUUGGCUCUGCAGAAAGGAUUUAAUGAAGUAAUUCCACAACAUCUGCUGAAGACAUUUGAUGAGAAGGAGUUAGAGCUCAUUAUUUGUGGACUUGGAAAGAUAGAUGUUAAUGACUGGAAGGUAAACACCCGGUUAAAACACUGUACACCAGACAGCAACAUUGUCAAAUGGUUCUGGAAAGCUGUGGAGUUUUUUGAUGAAGAGCGACGAGCAAGAUUGCUUCAGUUUGUGACAGGAUCCUCUCGAGUGCCUCUGCAGGGCUUCAAAGCAUUGCAAGGUGCUGCAGGCCCGAGACUCUUUACCAUACACCAGAUUGAUGCCUGCACUAACAACCUGCCGAAAGCCCACACUUGCUUCAAUCGAAUAGACAUUCCACCCUAUGAAAGCUAUGAAAAGCUAUAUGAAAAGCUGCUAACAGCCAUUGAAGAAACAUGUGGAUUUGCUGUGGAAUGACAAGCUUCAAGGAUUUACCCAGGACUCUAUUUAUACAACCCUGACUGACAGCCUCCUUUCAGCAGAGUUUCAAAGAAUAUGCUGAAAUACAGGAAAACACUCCCCCCCCCCCCCUUUUUUUUUUUUUUUUUACAUUUUAGGACACUGUGAGGGGAAAGGACAAUUUUGAAAUUCCUUUUCAAGGAAAAAAAAGGUCUUUAUGCUUUGCCAUGAGGCCACAUUCAGCUGCUAUUUAAACUUAAUAUCUUGAACCUAAAGAAUGCUGACUUUUCCUACAUUUCCAGAGUUAGGCAGUAUUCUACACUUAAAGACUACUACUAUUUUUAUAAAAGGUAAUCUAUUCAAAUUUCUUCACAGAUUUCAAGUCUCUCAAACAUCAAGACAACUUCAGCAGUCGGUACAAGUCACAUUUCAUUUUGAUUGAAUACAUGAUCUUGAACAGCUCCUGUACUUGCUCUUUGUAAAAAAAAAUAAAAUUAUUUUGAAUUAUUCUACCUUUGUAAACAAUUGGCUAAAAGAAUCAUCUUUAAGAAAUUAAGCCAUUUACAUGUUUGUGUUUUUCUAUAGCAGAGCAUUAUAUUUUGCAUUAUAUGUUUCAACCUAGUCUAAGUGGGUCUUUUUUACAUUUUUCAAGAACGGAUUUCCUGGAAUACAGCGAUAUAAUUUUGGUUGUCAAAUUCCUAAUGCAACCAUUUAGUCUAAACUUAGUCAUUUAUUUGUGACAAUAAGAUGUGUUCAGGGGCUCCCUGUUUUUAAGAGACUCUUUUAAAAAAAAAAAAACCUAAUGUUUUUAUCUUGAGUCAAUAUGAUUAGGUAUUUUGGAUUUACUUUUAAUCUUAAAAUACUGCAUUUUUAUAGCUUCUCAGAGCAUGUGGAUGGGAUGGGAUUUUCGUUAUUUUGCUGGGUCAGCUUAUCUUUAAUAUAUGGACUAUUCCUAUAAACCAAAGUCUCUGACAAGUGCACCUAAUUUAUAUUGUAUUUUAACUACAGUGUAAGUUUCCAUUAACAAAACCAUCCUAAAGCGUUAACUGCUCAUAAUUUUAAUCAGCUACAGUUAUGAAAAAGGAAGAAUUUUGCUCUAAAGAUUAUUAAUAAGCUUAGAAAAUCCUGCUUUUACCUAACAGAAUGAAGUGGGGUUGAGGGGCGGUAGUAUGAACAGUGAUUCUAACUCUAUGGCGUAAAUUACUUUGAAGAGUUCAUUUUGGAAGUAAGGGAAUCCCGCUUCCCUUGGUGUUGAAGAUCUGCAUCUGAUUUUGAAACGUCCAGAUUUAGCUUUCAAGGUGCGUGCAUGUUGAAUGAUCCAGAAGCAACGAAAACUCUGGGGUGAGGGAUUGAAAAAAUCUGAAAUCACAGUUGGAUUUUUAAAUUCAACCAUCAAAAAUAUGUACUAUCAGUUUUUUUUUACAUUGAUGUGAAAUAAGCAAAUUUUCAUGAUAAUUAAGCUGCAAAAUUUAAAGUUAUCAAGUAAAUAGGUCCUCUGUGUUCUGUUUCAUGUGAUGGAGUGGGUUUCAGUCUGUGUUCUUGGAGCCAAAGGGUUCCUCAGGGGUGCCUCAGGAGUAAUGGUUUAAGAGAAGAGGGGCAAUGAGAGGGAGCGAGGGGGAAGGCCUAGUUGGUAUUUGAGCAGGGGCCUUAGGCUCCAUAUCCCCACCCCCUUUACCCAGAACAGCCCAUUUUUCUUAUGUAUAUUGGAAUUUCAAGUAAGCUUUCAUGGGGUGCAGUGGGGCGGGGAGGAAUGGAUGGGAUAAAAAAAGUGGAGAUUUUGCUGCUUUAAAAAAGUUGAGAACUACUUGUGUAGUUUUUAAGUAUUUUAAUGUAUUUCAUUUGGCCAAAUUCAACUGCCACAAGCAAGCUAGUCAUAGUUGUAACUGUGCAGUGGUAAUAUGCUUAUGCCUACCUUUUUCCUCUCAAACAAUUUGUUUUUUUUACAUUGCAUUCUGAGUACUGAAGAGCAUCUUGAAAUGUAUGGAAGUGGUUUCUAUGCUAUUUGAUAAUCAGUAAUGUUCAGCUGUCAUGAUAGUACUUUACUGGUUGCAGACCCAUCUCUCUUUUAUAUUAAAGCACUAGUGCAGUUUAUAAUUGUGCCUACUUUUAAAAUCUUUCAGUAAAAAAGUACAUAAUGAAUACAGAAAUCAUAACUGACAGGGAUACAGUAAUAAUGAAAUGCUACUAUCACUUAUUUUAAUAUACAAUAUAAAGCAGGCAAAUACCAUUGCUUUUUGAGUGCCUUUUUAACUUUAUACUAAUGACUUAAUAGAGCUUUAAAAGAAAGAAAUUGGCUGGGCAUGGUGGCUCACACCUGUAAUCCCAGCACUUUGGGAGGCCGAGGUGGGCGGAUCACCUGAGGUCAGGAGUUCGAGACCAGCCUGGCCAACGUGGUGAAACCCUGUCUCUACUAAAAAUACAAAAUUUAGCCGGGCAUGGUGGCGCACUCCUGUAAUCCAACUACUUGGGAGGCUGAGGCAGGAGAAUUGCUUGAAUCUGGGAGGCAGAGAUUGCAGUGAGCCGAGAUCGCACCACUGCACUCCAGCCUGGGCGACAAGAGUGAGACUCCGUCCCCGCCCAAAAAAAAAAAAAAAAGAAAUUACUCUCCAUAACAGUCUAUGUUAUCACCAACAUAUAUAAAAACAUGAUUUAGAUUUCCAUUUCAAAGUUACAUUACCCGAUUACUUCCAAAUAGGUGCUAAGCAAAAACCCCCAAUGUAUUAUUGAACCAUGGACUUGCACCUCAUGUUUAAUGUGAAUAUUUAUUUCCAUGUCCCUCUUAACUGGUUUUUUCUUGUCUUCCCUCUAGCUGUAUUGUUAUUUCAGAUAUGUGAUAUCUGUUUUCAUACUCUUGCCUUUCCAUCAUGAAUGCUUAGUUAUGAACAGAGAUUCCUUUGUAGAGCUCAUAGGCAGUACAGAGAGGUAAGUCUUGCCUCAGAGGGCCUUGUAUCUUGGUGUAGUUUUUAAAUAGUGCAUAGUGUAUAGUGUAUAGUGUACAUUUUGUUUUGCACAUAGUUUGUUGCCCCGAAUGGGUUUUUUACCAAGCCUUUUUUUCUUUCAUGUAUUUACAGUCCGGAGCACAAGAUUCUCUUCUUUCAAAUACAAUGUAAUUCGCUUUACUUUACAACACUAAAUCUGGGCUUUGAAUUUCCAGUGCAUUGGACUGAUUGGAUUGUUGGGAGUUAGAGGCUGUUCCAACCAUCCUUAGUUUGGGAGAGUGGCUCCUUCUGCUUGUUUUCUAAGCGUACAGUCAACGGGUGCCAUUUGUGGUAUUUAACAUGUUAGGAUGAUUGUUCCAAAUGCUGAGUUGUUUUAUUUCUAGAUGUAAUUAGUUCACUUUAUGUAAUAUUCUUCUCUCAGACUGACUUUAAAAACAAAGUUUUAUCAUUUUCAUUGUAUUUGUAUUUAUUACAGAGUGUUUUAGCUUUGAUAUUCUUUGUAUUUUCAUUCAUUUGUUACAUGAGCUUUAUCAGUAACAUCUGUAUAAAUGGUUUUUAAAAAUUAACUAUGUAUGUGCCCAUGCCGAAGUCGAGCAAUAAAAUCAAUGCUGUUUGCACUGUCACAGCAUCAACGUUUUUAAAGAA